CUUCGCUCGCCGCCUCGCUCAGAGCCGGGGCCGGGCCAGAGCGGCGCCCCGCUGCCCUGUCCCCGCGUGCAGACCCCGGGCCCGGCCCCGGCCCCCCGCCAAGCCAUGCUGUGCGGCCGCUGGAGGCGUUGCCGCCGCCCGCCCGAGGAGCCCCCGGUGGCCGCCCAGGUCGCAGCCCAAGUCGCGGCGCCGGUCGCUCUCCCGUCCCCGCCGACUCCCUCCGAUGGCGGCACCAAGAGGCCCGGGCUGCGGGCGCUGAAGAAGAUGGGCCUGACGGAGGACGAGGACGUGCGCGCCAUGCUGCGGGGCUCCCGGCUCCGCAAGAUCCGCUCGCGCACGUGGCACAAGGAGCGGCUGUACCGGCUGCAGGAGGACGGCCUGAGCGUGUGGUUCCAGCGGCGCAUCCCGCGUGCGCCAUCGCAGCACAUCUUCUUCGUGCAGCACAUCGAGGCGGUCCGCGAGGGCCACCAGUCCGAGGGCCUGCGGCGCUUCGGGGGUGCCUUCGCGCCAGCGCGCUGCCUCACCAUCGCCUUCAAGGGCCGCCGCAAGAACCUGGACCUGGCGGCGCCCACGGCUGAGGAAGCGCAGCGCUGGGUGCGCGGUCUGACCAAGCUCCGCGCGCGCCUGGACGCCAUGAGCCAGCGCGAGCGGCUAGACCACUGGAUCCACUCCUAUCUGCACCGGGCUGACUCCAACCAGGACAGCAAGAUGAGCUUCAAGGAGAUCAAGAGCCUGCUGAGAAUGGUCAACGUGGACAUGAACGACAUGUACGCCUACCUCCUCUUCAAGGAGUGUGACCACUCCAACAACGACCGUCUAGAGGGGGCUGAGAUCGAGGAGUUCCUGCGGCGGCUGCUGAAGCGGCCGGAGCUGGAGGAGAUCUUCCAUCAGUACUCGGGCGAGGACCGCGUGCUGAGUGCCCCUGAGCUGCUGGAGUUCCUGGAGGACCAGGGCGAGGAGGGCGCCACACUGGCCCGCGCCCAGCAGCUCAUUCAGACCUAUGAGCUCAACGAGACAGCCAAGCAGCAUGAGCUGAUGACACUGGAUGGCUUCAUGAUGUACCUGUUGUCGCCGGAGGGGGCUGCCUUGGACAACACCCACACGUGUGUGUUCCAGGACAUGAACCAGCCCCUUGCCCACUACUUCAUCUCUUCCUCCCACAACACCUAUCUGACUGACUCCCAGAUCGGGGGGCCCAGCAGCACCGAGGCCUAUGUUAGGGCCUUUGCCCAGGGAUGCCGCUGCGUGGAGCUGGACUGCUGGGAGGGGCCAGGAGGGGAGCCCGUCAUCUAUCAUGGCCAUACCCUCACCUCCAAGAUUCUCUUCCGGGACGUGGUCCAAGCCGUGCGCGACCAUGCCUUCACGCUGUCCCCUUACCCUGUCAUCCUAUCCCUGGAGAACCACUGCGGGCUGGAGCAGCAGGCUGCCAUGGCCCGCCACCUCUGCACCAUCCUGGGGGACAUGCUGGUGACACAGGCGCUGGACUCCCCAAAUCCCGAGGAGCUGCCAUCCCCAGAGCAGCUGAAGGGCCGGGUCCUGGUGAAGGGAAAGAAGUUGCCCGCUGCUCGGAGCGAGGAUGGCCGGGCUCUGUCGGAUCGGGAGGAGGAGGAGGAGGAUGACGAGGAGGAAGAAGAGGAGGUGGAGGCUGCAGCGCAGAGGCGGCUGGCCAAGCAGAUCUCCCCGGAGCUGUCGGCCCUGGCUGUGUACUGCCACGCCACCCGCCUGCGGACCCUGCACCCUGCCCCCAACGCCCCACAACCCUGCCAGGUCAGCUCCCUCAGCGAGCGCAAAGCCAAGAAACUCAUUCGGGAGGCAGGUCAGAAGAGAGUGAGGAGCGGGGGCAGGGUGACCUGGGGACGGGCUUGGGCUCUGUUCCCUGGAGGUUACAGGCCGGGGCUUUGGGUGAGGGACCCCCGGAGUCUGUCACGGUCUCACCCCAACUCUGCCCCAGGGAACAGCUUUGUCAGGCACAAUGCCCGCCAGCUGACCCGCGUGUACCCGCUGGGGCUGCGGAUGAACUCAGCCAACUACAGUCCCCAGGAGAUGUGGAACUCGGGCUGUCAGCUGGUGGCCUUGAACUUCCAGACGCCAGGCUACGAGAUGGACCUCAAUGCCGGGCGCUUCCUAGUCAAUGGGCAGUGUGGCUACGUCCUAAAACCUGCCUGCCUGCGGCAACCUGACUCGACCUUUGACCCCGAGUACCCAGGACCUCCCAGAACCACUCUCAGCAUCCAGGUGCUGACUGCACAGCAGCUGCCCAAGCUGAAUGCCGAGAAGCCACACUCCAUUGUGGACCCCCUGGUGCGCAUUGAGAUCCAUGGGGUGCCCGCAGACUGUGCCCGGCAGGAGACUGACUACGUGCUCAACAAUGGCUUCAACCCCCGCUGGGGGCAGACCCUGCAGUUCCAGCUGCGGGCUCCGGAGCUGGCACUGGUCCGGUUUGUGGUGGAAGAUUAUGACGCCACCUCCCCCAAUGACUUUGUGGGCCAGUUUACACUGCCUCUUAGCAGCCUAAAGCAAGGGUACCGCCACAUACACCUGCUUUCCAAGGACGGGGCCUCACUGUCACCAGCCACGCUCUUCAUCCAAAUCCGCAUCCAGCGCUCCUGAGGGCCCACCUCACUCGCCUUGGGGUUCUGCGAGUGCCAGUCCACAUCCCCUGCAGAGCCCUCUCCUCCUCUGGAGUCAGGUGGUGGGAGUACCAGCCCCCCAGCCCACCCACUUGGCCCACUCAGCCCAUUCACCAGGCGCUGGUCUCACCUGGGUGCUGAGGGCUGCCUGGGCCCCUCCUGAAGAACAGAAAGGUGUUCAUGUGACUUCAGUGAGCUCCAACCCUGGGGCCCUGAGAUGGCCCCAGCUCCUCUUGUCCUCAGCCCACCCCUCAUUGUGACUUAUGAGGAGCAAGCCUGUUGCUGCCAGGAGACUUGGGGAGCAGGACACUUGUGGGCCCUCAGUUCCCCUCUGUCCUCCCGUGGGCCAUCCCAGCCUCCUUCCCCCAGAGGAGCGCAGUCACUCCACUUGGCCCCGACCCCGAGCUUAGCCCCUAAGCCCUCCUUUACCCCAGGCCUUCCUGGACUCCUCCCUCCAGCUCCGGAACCUGAGCUCCCCUUCCCUUCUCAAAGCAAGAAGGGAGCGCUGAGGCAUGAAGCCCUGGGGAAACUGGCAGUAGGUUUUGGUUUUUAUUUUUUGAGACAGGGUCUCGCUCCGUCGCCCAGGCUGGAGUGCAAUGUUGCAAUCAUGGCUCACUGCAGCUUUGAACUCCCAGGCUCAAGCGAUCCUCCCAUCUCAGCCUCCUGAGUAGCUGGGACUACAGGCACAGGCCACCAAACCUGGCUAAUGUUUAAAUUUUAUGUAGAGAUGGCGGGGGGGGCGGGGGUCUCCCUAUGUUGCCCAGGCUGGUCUCGAGCUCCUGACCUCAAGUGAUCCUCCUGCCCCAGCAUUCCAAAGUGCUGGGAUUACAGGUGUGAGCCACUGCCUGGCCUGGCCGUAGGUUUGUAACUGUUUCAUAGAAGAGCCCUGGAGAAGACAGUAGAAUGAGCCUAUCUAGUUUAAAAAAUAAAGAAGCACGUUGAUUUCACCACCGCCACUCCCUGAGCACCUCUAUGCUGCCACCCCCACAGGCCCAUGAGGAGGGACAGGGCUGGAUGAGUUUCUUGGGCCUCUCCCCUCAACAGGGCAUGGACUUGGCUAAGACAGCCAGGGGGUGGCAGCAGGAGAUGCCACAGCUCUAAAUAGCCCGAUCCCUGCUCCUGGCUUAAAGCUGCUGCGAGUAUCACAAGACUGUCUGAGGAUGCCAAUUCAGCAGGUCAGCGCCUCCCCACAACACACACACACACACACACACACACACACUCACACAUACACAGAGGGGCCUUGAAUGAGGAGGAGACAGGAGUCUGAGGGACCCUCAGACUGCCACUCUCCAGGCUUGGCUGGGCUCAAGGCCCCUGUCUGCUCAGUAGGGCAAAUCCCAAGGACACGGGCUUCCCUUCCUCCAGCCAGCCAGCCUUUUACACAAAGGCUGGAAACGCUGCUUGGGCCGCCUCUAUAGAAAUGCCAGGAGAGCGCACUGGACACUAGGCGACAGAAUCUGGAGAAAAUCCUGCACCCGCCCCUGCCAGCAGGGUGAAAUGUGGAGGCCUGGUGUUUUAGGUUCUGCCAGCCAACAGUGCCGGCACUGGACAAGGGCAGAACUUGACAUUAGUCCCCAGAGGGUGGCCUGGAACUGGGCUGGGAUAGGCCUUGAACUGGCCCCAAGCCCCACAGAAACCAAAACACAGGGCUGGGGCAGACUCCACCUUCUAGCAACUCCAAGAACUAAUGCAGAAAGUGGCAGUGUCCCCCGCUCCUUCAUGCUGGGAGUGGCGUUUGGCUCUGGUUAAUUUGUGUGUCUGAAAGAGGAUAAUCAGAAUCAAAAGGGCCCAGAAGGAAUGGGCCGAGCCAGGCGGGCCGGGCCAGGCAGCCCGGGCAUCUGGCACUCAGGGCUGUCAGAGGGUCAGGCUGCCAAACUGCAGCCUCAGGAUGGGAGGCACAGUGAGGCUAAGUCCAGUUUUAGCAAAUGAAGAGCCAUUAGCAUUGCCCAGCCCCUGCAGAGCCAGGUCUGGCCAGGGGCUGGCUGGGGGGUCUGGGUCAGGUGAGCACCAGACCCAGGGCUGAGUGCCCAUCCUGCUUGGCUUCUCUGGUUUCGUAUCUGGUACCAAGAGGAAGGGGUGAAGGCUAGGAUGAGGGCCCAAUACUGAGAAGGCUGCCUUGAAAGGGCAAGAGUCUUUUUUUUUUUUCUUUUGAGACAAAGUCUUGCUCGUCCCCCAGGAUGGAGUGCGAUGGCGUGAUCUCGGCUCACUGCAACCUCUGCCUCCCGGGUUCAAGCGAUUCUCUUGCCUCAGCCUCCGGAGUAGCUGGGAUUACAGGCGCCCGCCACCAUACCCAGCUAAUUUUUGUAUUUUUAGUAGAGACGGGGUUUCACCAUGUUGGCCAGGCUGGUCUCGAACUCCUGACCUCAGGUGAUCCACCCGCCUUGACCUCCCAAAGUGCUGGGAUUACAGGCGUGAGCCACUGCACCCAGCCAAAAGGGCAAGAGUCUUUAAGGAAGUGAACUGGGAAGCAGAAGCAAGGGAGAAAUCACAGGGUUUUUUUUUUGUUUGUUUUUUUGAGAUGGAGUCUCGCUCUGUCGCCUAGGCUAGAGUGCAGUGGCACGACCUUGGCUCACUGCAAGCUCCGCCUCCCGGGUUCACACCAUUCUCCUGCCUCAGCUUCCCAAGUAGCUGGGACUACAGGCGCCCACCACCAUGCCCGGCUAAUUUUUUUGUGUUUUUAGUAGAGACAGGGUUUCAUAGUGUUAGCCAGGAUGGUCUCGAUCUCCUGACCUCGUGAUCCACCCGCCUCGCCCUCCCAAAGUGCUGGGAUUACAGGCGUGAGCCACCAUGCCCAGCCUGAAAUCACAGCUUUUUAUCCCAGAGGCCCAUGGGUAGAAACAACACAUAGGGCUAUGUUCUCUCAGCCCAAAGCUAAGGGCAGGAAAAAAGGCAUGGGCCAUAGGAGCCUGAGUGACUUGGUUUGGGACAGGAGGGUUGGGGGGCUUUAGAGGGGUCAGGCAGGUCCUGUGUCCUCUCAGUUUCCCUGGAAAGGGGCUUGGAGGCACCAGUCAUGGACCUGAAAGGAUCAGGGGGUCAGGGAAUGGGUAAGUUCCAGAGGAUGAGAAGAGGGGGAAUGGGAAGUCUUAAACACAGCUACUGGGGCCCAGCAACUUGCCAUGUUAAAAUGCACCCCUAGUGACUCAAAGAACCACCCGGCCAGUGGUGCAGGAGGAGAGAUGUGGCACCUGGGCACAGUGGGAAGGCACGGGGCCUGCACCUCCACCAGAGGAGCCACUGCUGACCUGGACCAAGGGGGCUGCUCUGUGCCCAGCUAGGGAAGCCUGGGCCGGCUCCUGUGCUGAGGUGCUCAGGUGCUGGCUGAGAGCCCAGUUGCUGCUCUAACUUGGAGUGAACCUGGGUCAAUAGCAGCUCGUCUCUGGCGGGUGGGAAGGGUCUGACAACACCAAGUUUGCCCUGGAAGAAGGGCAGCCUUAAAGGAAGGCCUUUGGAAGCUGGCCUGGUGCUGUGGGCUUGAGGGACUUUGUGUCCAAGCCCUGUCGUCCUGGCUCCAGCCUAGGCUCCAGCACUCCAUUUCUUCCACUGCCACCUGCUGACCAGGAAUACCAGGACAGAAGGUUUUGUUCAGCUGCUUUCUUUAUUAGAAACAAGUGAGAUGUAUUGAGCAGAACAACAA